CUUUUCGACUUCAGACUGAGAGCAUAUAGUCCACAUUUCAGGUGUUUCUUGGGUUUGUUCCCUGCUGCCCCCUUUCAGUGUGGUUAUGUUAUUCAUUUGAAAUACAAUUUGGUUCCUUUGUUUCUCUUUGUAUUCUAUUUGAGAGAUUUCCCCAAUCUUAGGGAUUUUCUCUUCCCUCCCUUUUGUGUGAACCACGGACAUUUCCAAAAGGCAGGUCUGUACAAAAAGUUCUAUUCAGAGAGGUGCUCCCCCUCCUUUCCACUCCAAUCCCUUUUUCCUCUCUACCCAGCUCCCACCCUGCCCUGUAGGGAACCAGUCUCAUUAGUCUGUGUUUUUUCCUUCUAUGUUUCUUUUUGCUUUAAUGAGUAGUUUCUUAUUCCGCUCUUUUUCUUCAUAAAAAGUAGAAUAUUCUGAAUCCUCUUUCACAGUUUGCCGUUUCUCAUUUAACUGUGCGCCUGAGCAGGCUACAUUAGUCCUGAGGGGUCCCUGAUCCUUCCUUCUGCUCCUGAGGGGUCUGUUGUGGUCUCCAUUUUGGCUGUUAUGUAGGUGCAUGAGAACUGUGCAGUGUGCGUCUAGGUGCUAAUGACAGCACAGCCCCCACCAGGCGUUGUGUCUUUUCCACCUGACUCUGGAAGAGUGGUAAUGUGGGCAGAGGAGGAAACUGAGGCUCAAAGUAGUCCCAUGACCACACGUCACACAGAUGUGAGCUGGUCCUAGAGGUUGAGGCCAGACUGUCUGGUGCCAGAACUGAAACUUGUGAAUGACGGGUGUACUUGCUCCUCCUGCUGGGGUUCAUUGCAUGCCUGAGAUGCCAAGAGCAGGGCUCGCAUCACCCUGGGUGCUAAGGAAAAAGGCCCCAGGGAGGGAAGGAUAACCCAGGAGAAAGGAGGAGCUAUUCCCCUUAUAAUUGCUUUCCUUAUCAUUCUUUUAAAAUUUGUUGUGUGUACAUGUUUUGUAAUGAGUAUAACACAUCAAUAGAAUAGGGUUUAUGUACUCAAAGUUGUGUGCUCAGAAAAAUUUUUAAAAAUGAUAGUGAUAUGUGAUCAAAAAAGUUUGGAGAUCACGGAAAGAGAAGCUCACUCAGCUGUCUUGAAGUGGAGAGAGCCCUGGCCUGGCCUUAACAUCCAGAGAUGAGGGCUUGUGAUCCCACCUGCUCCUGCUAUGGGGGCAACAAGACAUUCAUUCACUCAAUCAUUCGUUCAUUCAUUCAUUCAUUCAUUCAGUAUGGCUGAGCGGUGAGGUUAACACAGUGAGCAGGAAGGUGCUGUCCUGACUUCAGAGAGCAUCUGCAAGUCCAGAUGGGGAUCUUCAUGGCUGGAAGGACAGUGAGGCCUGUCAGGGAAGGACACAGUGCUGUGGAUCACCUAGGAGGGGCUUGUAAGUGAGGUUUGGGGGUUAGAUGUGACUUCCAGGGAGAAGAGUGACGCCUAAGUGUGUAUGAGAGUCCUCUGGUGUGAGGCUUGGAGAGGAGGGAGUGUAGCUGCUGGCCAGCACCGUGGAAGAGUUGACUCUGAGCAAAUCAUUAAUCUUUUUGGGCCUUAAUUGUCUUCUCUGUAAUGGGGAAGGAUAGUACCACUGGCCUCUCCAGCAAGUUCUUUGCAUCUGCUGAGGCCAGAUUCAGGUGUCAAAUUCUCAGCUCUGCUGUUGACUAGCCAUGUGUCUUUGGGAUGUGUUAUGUCUGGAGCUUUGCUAACAAAGCUUUCUCACCUUAUCUCAUUGAGUCCUCCCAUCCAGCAUUUUCCAUAUGAGUGCUUUGAGUUUCAGAGAAGUGAAGCGCUUAUGGAGGGUCCCACAAGCAGUGGGAGCCGGGACGCAGGGCUGACUACUACACCUGGGCCCGCCUUUUCACCACAGACUGUGUGUGCUUGUCAUACUUAGACUUUGCUUGUACUUGGGAAAGGAGUUCAGUUUGCUUUAAUGUCACUUUAAUGCUUUUUAGAAUUCAUUUCCUUUGUUUAUUUUGCAGCGGUAUAAUUUGCAAUGAAAUAGUUUCACAUUGAGCUUACAUGUUUUGAUGGCAUCUUAAUGUUGGCUCCAUGGAUUUGCAGCCAGAUACUUUUGUCAUUCUAACUUUCCUAUAUGAUGGCACUAUGUGGCAGUGUGGCCAUGAACUAUGGCCUGGGUUUCCCUUUAGGCCGGCCAGGUAGCCUCUGAGUCAGGUGUUCGGUGUCUCUUGGGUCGUGGAGGACUCUGCACACUGGGGACAAGUGUCCUGUGUGUCAGUCUCCUGUGUAGCUUGGUUUUACUUUGCCAUGUCAUUGGGUCCUUCCUGGGGUUGGGUUUCACCUAGGAACAUCUGGCUGGGCAUCAUAUGUGCAGAAGAGAGCGUCUCUUCGCUCUCGCCCCCUGAGCUGUGGAGGGUACAUGCGCACCCCAGAAGCAAAAGCUCUGGCUCCCAGAGGGCCUUGGUUUGCUAGGUUGGCCCUGCUUUCAGUUGCUGUCCUUGUGCCACAGCAUAUGCUGAGCCAUCUGUUCUGCCUUUUUGUUUUGGAAAAUGUGGCACAACAGUUAGAGUCUUGCCUAGAAGAGCACUGAAGGCCUUUUAGCACUGGGGCUGUGCCUUAGCCAUUUGGGUCCCUUCAGUGCUUGGUGAGGGGCUGGAGCUGGAGUAAGGGCCUGGUACUUGUGUGUUGAAUGCUUGUAUGCAUGUUUGAUUAUUGUGGCUGAGGGCUCAGGAGAGUGGCAGGAAAGGAGGAGGUGGAGCCCAGAGCAGGGACUUCUUUCCAGGGCCCAACCCACACGUUGGUCUUGCUCCUGGAAGAGCACCUGCCUGUAGAAAGCAGGUCCCUUCUGCCCAGCCCCCCACGGCCCAGCCUUAGCCCCAUCCUCUCCUCAAGAGACCCCACAGCUUGGCUUUAGCAAGACCCAGACCCAUAUCUGAGAUUCCAGUCUGAGCCCGCUGAGUGUUGAGUCUCACUGUUUCAGCUCUUGGGUUUCAGUGCCCAAGAAGUGGUACUAUAGUGGCAUAAAAAAGCCACCCGAAGCUGGGCUCAUACCUUAGCUUUGGCACUUACUAGCUGUGUGGCCUUGGGCAAGGUGGGUUGCUUAACUUCUGGCAGCCUUGAUUUCCUUACUGUGAAGCAGAGACAUACCUCUAAGCAGAGAGUGGUUGUAGGGAUUUGGGAUGACAUGUGUCCAGCACCCAGACACUUGGGCAUUGGUUGCCAUUAUUAUUAUUAGUAUUAUUACUAGUAUUAUUAGUAUUAGUAGUAUUACUGUUACUGCUACUGAUGUUACUGUCACCACCACUGUUAACCCCCAUUCUCUCCCUCUACCUCUCCAACCCUACGUUCACCCACAGCACUGGUGUUAUACGCCCCCUUAGUGAAGAAGAGAAGACAGGAGCUGGCUCAGAGCAUUUAUCUGCCCAGCUGCUGUGAGCCCUGAGCUGACCACCAAGGAUGCUAAGGGGUUCAAGGAGGACUGCACCUCCCUCUGUCCUUGCCUUCUCAUCCUUUUUUCUCCUGACACACCAUUGUUUUCGCAAAAGAAAGAAGUAGUUGGAGUCUGGGAAAGAAAUCCCCAGGGCCCUGUUUCAGAUGAUUGUCCCAUUUCUAAACUUGAGUUAAUAAGAGUAAACAAAGUAGUAGGUAGAUUUGCACAGGAGAAUAUUAUUAUUCUCAUGAUUAUGUAAAUAUUUAUCUGUUCUGGCUUUCUUAUUUUGUUGCUGGUGUCUAAUUUCCAAGUCUUGUAAUGAAGUGUAAUUUGGAGAAGAUUUGCAAAGACAGGCACGUAGUGAAAUAAUUUGAUUUGUUCAGUAAACUUGGUUUCAGUUAUUCCUUUCCAUGAGUUGUUUUAGAACCCCUUCAAUUUCUUUGUGAUUUGACAACAGCUUUCAGCCCAAUGAAGAUAUGACUCUUAGGCAUUGCCAGGAAUUCAGAAUUGGUUUAUAAUAUUGUCGCUUAAUAAGAAAAUGCGUUCAUUGGCAGGAUAUAAAAUUUAUGGGCUUCAAAUGGAUUUCUGUUUGUAGUUUUAGCCCUCUGUGCUCCUGCCAUUCUCGAGGCUAUGAGUAAGGUUUUUUAAUUAAGUCAAAUUGAAUUGAAUGAGCUUUUAUUGAACGCCCACUCUGUGCCAGACACCAGCUCCUUAACCCUUGCACUGCCCUGUAGGUGGCUAUGGGGAGCUGAGCCAGAGGAGGUUUUGCCCCAUGCUCACGAUCAUUCAGCUGGCAAACCUGGGAGGUGGGAUUUGAAGUUAGGUUUGAUUCUCUGGCUUUUUCAUCCAAAGCUGAUUAUAGGCAGACUUGAUUAAGGAGAAGAGAGAGGUUGAGUGGCUUUCAUGUUAUUUCAUUGAAUCUUGUUUAGUCUUCUCAGCCACCCUGUGAGGUUCAUUACAUUUUCCCUAUUGUAUAUCUGAGGAAAGUAAGGCUCAGAGAGGUACAGUGAUAUGCUCAGGGUCACACAGCUGGUAAGAGGCAGAGCUGGGAUUUGAACUCAGAACUGCCUGGCUGCAAGGCCAGAGUUCCUUCUAGAACCCCUCUAGGGGUCUGCACUUCCUUUAGCACAUGGCCAAUUGACCACCUGCCCACAAAAAAUGGCCUGGCCCUGGUGGCUAGGGCACCCUCCUGCAGAUGGAGGCAAGGAGCAGUAGGGAGUGGGGCUGGGCAUCAGUUGCCCAGGUACUUCCUAGCUCUAUGCCCUGGGCAAGUGAAGUCCUCCUUUCUGACCCUCCCUGCACCCACUGGUGACUGGUGGCAGAAUACCCUCCUGGGUUAUUGUUAGGAUCACAGACAACAUGUGUGAGGCACCUGGCACUUGGUGGGCACUCAGGAAGUGAAGGACCCUGCCCUUUGGCAUCUGUUGCUUGUCAGAAUGCGUGGUGGAUGGCUCUGGCCUCGGUGACGAAGCUGCUGUUGCUUCAGCCCCCGGACUCCUGUGCAUCACAGAGCUGAUUCAGUGCAGACAGGUGACUCAUCUGAUGGCAUUUUGUGUGGCGUUGUGCAGUUCAGCCUGGUACAGCACGGCCCGCCCACAGCAGGUAUUCAAGAGCCGUUAGUGUUUAUGAAGGUGAUAAAAUUGCCUAGAUGGAGGGAAGCCGUCAAAAUAAGAGCCUUUGCCUGUCUUGUGAAAGUUAACUUGCAAACCUAAUGCCUGUGGGGCUGCUGAAAAAGCGUCACCUGGAUUUCUCCUUGGAGACAGAACUCUCUGGAAGGACAGCUGGGCAGCCCCUGCUUGCCAUGUGGGGGUGGACGCUUUUUAUGUGACAGUGAGUUGGAGAAACUAACAGUGGUCUUCAAGGCAUUGUGCUCAGCUUAACUCUUUGAAUUGCCAUAGCUUUAAAAUGAAUACUAGAAACAGUUAUAUAUUUUUCACACUCUCCAUAUUUUCUCCAUUCAAUAUAAUAAAUGUUAUCUUGAAUGUUUGAGGGUUUUAUAGCAAAAAUUCCUCCCAUUUGUAAAGCAUGCUGCAGUGGAUGGGAGUGAACUAGCUGGCAGCGCUCUCGUGUGACGUGGCAGAGGCUGAGGGAGUUGCCCAAACCCCACUUCCAGUUGGAGGAAGCCUGGGCCCUGACUUCCAGUGCAUGUUCAGGUCCACUUGUCAAGGAAAGGAUCCAUUGUUAAGAAACAAACAUGGGAAACUGUCAUGUGAGCGUCCCUAAAAGCAGCAUAGUCAUUUUCGAGUCACUCUCUGAUAAAGAUAGAACACUUCAUUUAGGCACAUUUCAGGAUUUCAGAACAUUUGGAGUAGUCCUGGGGUGGAAAGCAGCGUUUUCCUUUUUCAAUUUCAACCUGACUCCAUUCCUCUCUUUAUGUGUGUCAGUCAUAGCAGGGGAGUGUUUUCCUCUUGGAUGCGUUUGCACCUGGCAAAUGAAUGUGCAGGAAUUCUUUGAUUGCAAAAUAGCUACUCUCAAAAUGCAGACAGGCAGCCACAGUCAGGGAGCCCUUCGGCCACGGCAGCGGGGUGGCGCCAGACACCUGGCUUUGAGUCCCGUGGAGGCAUGCCACUUAGUCUGUUCUGAGCGGCUGUUUACAGGCGGAUAGAAAGGGCUGUAGGAUGGGACCCUCAAGGUUUUGGGGCAUGGGAGGGGCUGGCCGUCAUGAUUCAGCAUGCUAGCUCUCUGGAGGCUGUGCUGAGCACUGAGGGACACUGGGAGAAAAACACAGGCUCCUGCUUUGUCCAUGUGGAAGGAGCCCAGGCUGCCCUGGCUGCUAUACGCAUCCUUCCAGGCAACCUUCACCUUCUGGUCUAUUUAGUCUCAUUCCCUGUUUUUAUUCCCUUCUUUUAUUUAGGGAGAGCCAGAGCAGCAAUUCUCAGGUCAGGAUUAUUUGGGAGAUCCAUAUUACUUCUGAUUAUUUACGAAGGGACAGGCCGGGGGAGGUAACCACCUCGAUAAAUUCGUCAGCGAGGCAGCUGGAGGGAUGUGUGACAAACAUACCAGGCUGUCAUUUGGCCAGAGAUUGUCUGCACUGGGAUUGUUCCCCCAGGAUAGUCCUGAUGACAAAUGUAAUUGACAUUUUUUAUUAACCCUGAAAUGAUUAAAGAUGCUGCUGCUGAAUUUGUGUCAAAGUACCCGGUCCCUGGCAUUUUGAGAAAGGGAUUCUCUGUGGAGCCAAUAAACAGCCUGUGUUUUCUUCCUGUUCAUCACUUUAAUCAACUAAGACAUACAGAGCCCUGUCUGGUUUGGUCUUGAAACUGGGCCAGGGAGAUAAGACUCUGCUUCCUGGCUUAGGUUUCCAGAACACUCUGGUAUGGACAUCAUGAGGGACACAUAGGAGGCACUCUGUUCAUUUACCACACAGUCAUCAAACGUUUGCUGAGCUCCUUCUGUGUGCCAGGUCCUGUGUGUGAUAUUGGGCGCUGUCUCCUUGAAGGGUGGUCGCUGUAGAAUGGGGGCUAGAAAGAUGUUUAUGGGGAUGAUUGUGAGAACUGAGCAUUGUAGGGGAAGACUGGGCCACCCUCACUGCCUAGGGGGUGGGGUGGGGCAGGGAAGGCAGUGCAGGGGGUGGUUUGCGUCUUACAGGAAGGGAGUCUCCUCUCCAGACAGGUCUUACCUCUGGAGCUCUCCAGGCAGAUGCUGGAAGUGGCAGUGCCCAGAGUGUGUGGGUCUUGGAGUGCCAGAGUGUGGGAACACAGAGGGGCAGCAGGGGAGGGUGGAAGACACACAGGAGAGCUUGGCUGGGGCCUGCAGAUGGGCUGGGGGCCACAUGGAGCGCAGGUGGACUUUGCUGCUUCCUAGCCUGCCUGCUGAGUUACUGAAGCUCUUGGUCUUGGUUUCCUUAUCUGUGAAAUGGGACAAUCCUACUUUCGCUUCUGUCAUAGGGCUGCUGCAGGAUGAAAUGACAGUAGGAGGAAAGCCCCUGAUUGGUGCUUGGCAUACAGAGCCUAGUCAACAAGCAUCGGUUCCUUCCUAGAUGCAGUCUCAGUAGCAGUGGCCAGGUAUUGAGCACCUACUGCAUGCCAAGCGCUGGGCUGAAGGCCUUGCACUGACUCUCUGUUAGGUAUUUUUAUUCCCAUUUUAUAGCUGAGAAACUUGUUAGAGGGUAAAGCAGUUGCUCAGGGUCACACAUAGAGAGAGGCAGAGAGAAGAUCUGACACCAGGCUGUUGCUCCCAAGGGCUUCCUUUCAGCAGUGCAGGGGCUGGGAGGUGCCAGGAGGAGCAGGAACAUGGAGAGGGCCAGCUUUGACUGUGGCCAGAGCCAUGCUUGAGCUCUUCUUUUGGAGGGAUGGGCUUGGGUUGCAGAGGGUCUUACAGGGAGAGUGUGCUUAUCACACUGCUCCUGGAUGGACUGAUGAAUUGAACACUUCCUGAGCACCUGUUUUGUGGCUAGCCCUCUGCUGAGGGUGCACACAUUCCCUCAGCCACAAAGCCAGUAUUUAGUGAGCACCUACUGCAUGCCAUGUGGUCCACCAGGCCUUGGGUAGAUGGUGGUGUACCAGAGGCAGGGGUCUUCACCCUGGGGGAGCUCCCAGGCUGGCAGGGAAAGAAGGAAAGAAAAAGAUCACACAUCUAGCAUUGUGGAUAAGCAACAUUUCAGCACUGAAAUAGUGGGUCUAUGUUAUUAACAUUUUAUAUGCUAGGCUCUCCCACACAAAACCAGAUCAGAACCCUCUCUCUUGCCCCUGAACUGCAUAGGUUUCAAAGGUGAUCUGUCCCCUUGUAUCUCGACCUGUUGCUCAGGAACCAUUCCCAUCAGUUUAAUUUCUUUUUCCUUUUAAUCCUGUGGCUGGCAGGAUGUUGCAGGGGCAGUAAUUUAAUAAAAGUAUGCAGUUUGUAAAGCAGCUGCUAUUCUGUGUACUAAGCACAUUUGCCAACCUUUUCAGGGAAACCUCCAAGCUGUUCUUGGAACUUAGCGAUAUUGCAGGAAAAAAAACAUUCUAUUUAAUAACAUUUCAUCCUUUGGGUUCUGCAGCUAAUAGAAGCAUAAAUGGAGGCCAUGUCUGAAAGCCAUUUCUUUAUGUGAUUCAGAGAAUCAGGACAUAGCAAUUACACAGUGUAUGGGAUUUAUGGAAACAUUCAUGCCUAACAAGAAGAAAACAGCUCAGUAAGUUAUUUAAUUUGAAGUCACAGGCCCGCUGACUGGUUCCCCACCCAGACCUACCGCACUGCUCGGCAGGCCCCAGGCGCUCGCACACAGGUGCCCACUGCUCCCUGUCUCUCUGAGUCCUGCCCGGCUGCAGGUGGAAACCUGGGCCUGCUCUGUGGGGUGUGUUCACACCUUAGGCCAGGGCAAGGUGGAGCUGGGUUUGAAUAUUGCUCUUCUGACUCCAAGCCUGUCUUUCCUCACCACUGCAUAUAACAGCCUCAUUAGGUUUGUAAUACGUGGCAGCUGCAUGAUCUGCUGGGUAAGAGACACACAUUUAGAAAAAUUUAUGUGCCACAUGCUUUUCCUUUCUUUAUUUCUCUUUCCCCUGAACUGAGAUAAAAAGGAGAGUCACACACAAGCAGAUGUCAGAAUGACUGCCUUGCUUCGCCCCAUCUACUGGAAAAGCCACCGACUGAAUUCUUCCUAACACCGUUUCUGUUUAUGGCAGAUAUAGGGUGGGGGUGGGGGGCAGGGCCCUCCAUUCUCUGCUUUCCGUGCUAGCCGAAGCCUUAAUUCAAAAACAAAUUGAGUCCUUCAGCUGUCACUCGAUUGUUCCCUCUGAUUUUGGGGGAUAAAUAUCAUUGCUGCAGCCUCAUGUCUCCUCUCUCUCCUUUUCCCCAAAGCUUUUCCCCUUUUAUUUUCUCUCUCUGCCCAGAACUCAACAUAUCUCUGACAAAAGCAUGCAUUAUUUAGAGCCUGUCGCCUCUUGAAGUUCUUUAAUUACAGAAUUAAACCAAAGUAAUGACAGUUUAAUUUGUUCUUUCAUUAAUUGGGAGCGCUCCGGGCUGAUGUGAAAUGAGCGCAUUUGGAAGGCAUGAGGAAUAUGUACUGAGUGAUUGGAGCAUGAGUAAUAAUAAUUGCUGUCGUUUAGUGCCGGGCGCUGGCUAGGUGCUCCUCAUGCAUAUUCUCUGUUAAUGCUCCCUGCAACCUUGAGGAGGAGAUACCACCUUCUCUGUUUUGCGGCUUAGGAUCUUGAGGCUCAGAGAGGUGAACCAACAGCCACCUGUCAGCCAGAGGAAGAGCCAGGCCUAGACACCAGGAGCCCAGCCCCAGAGCCUUAUCCUGUCCAUAGCCCCACUUGGCCUUGAGACCAGCAGCUGUGGCCUCAGGAUUCUGCAAGGGGUGGCCCACAGGAAGAUGGGCACACCUGGCGGGGCAUGCCUGAGAAGGACUAAGUUGUGUCUGGCUGAAUUUGAGGCUGAGAGGAAACAUUUGAACCCGUGAAAAUGGAAGGAAAUUGGCGGUCAGAGGGAGCUGAAGCCUCACUGGUGCUGAUGGAAAUUUUGCUACUUCGAAGGUAGCAGUUUGUCCUCCCGGGAGCCCUGCAGCCACUGAGGGGCAUGCCUGCGAGUGCAUCCGUGCCACUUAGUUGUGGGUCAGGGAGGCUGCUGCAGGGAACCGCAGGAUGGACAUCUCUAAAGCAUAUAGUGAAGGGUAGAAUCCAGGUGUAUGGGGCCCCGUCAGGCCUGCUGGUCCCCCUUACCCUAGCUAAGGCCCAUGCCAGAGCUGCUACCUUUCCAUGGACACGUCUGGGUCCAGGUGACUUCCUUCUUGCACUGGCCCCAGGCCCCAGGCCCCAGGCCCCACCGUACCUGGCAGAUGAAGUGCCUCUGAUGCCCCUCCGUGGCCUGCAGAAGUUCUGGGUUGGGCCUUUGGUUUCAGGCCCCUGGGACUAUACAGAGGGUGGAUGGUUGGUGCAUUCACAGUACUAGUGGCUCAUCUGGAGGGCUGUGUCUAGAAGGAGGCAGCGGCGAAACAGCUCAUCGUCCUCCUCACGUCCUUAGGGACUUGAGCCUGGUGUGUACCGACACUGCGCUCUCUUGGCAGCAGGCAGUGAGGGACAGGAGAAGAACCAAAGUUGAUAGUGCCUUCUGUGGCACCUUCUACUUCGUCACUUUAAUUCCCUUUAAGCUUCCCCACCACUCUGGAAAGUGGGAAGAUUAGCCCCGUUUUCUAGCUGUUGAAAUGAAAGCUCAGAGACAAUGGUCAUUUACCCAGGCCACAUGGAUUGAAGGGGCAGAACAGAGUUAGGAUUCAGGGGUGUCUGACCCUGAAGUCCCCCAUGGAACUGGGCCUCUGUGUUCUUGCUGUCACCCCAUAUCCCCACCAGGCACCCUCUCACUCACUCUGUUCACAUCUCCCAGCAACCUCAGAGUUUUACCCUAUGAGUUCUCAGACAAAACUUUAGAAUUUAUUAUCAAUGCAUUUCUCUGCAGCAAAGUCUGGAUGAAUUUAAGAUUAGGGGAUUCGGUUACACUUUAUUACUGUUUGUCAUUAAAAAUCAUGCAAAUAAGCCAUGGAAUAAAGUAACUUGUGUUGUUUUGGACACCAGAUUUACAUGUUUACUGGAAGAAAAAUGAUGCUGAACUCCUUCAAGGUGGUAAUAAAAUUUUGCCUCAGAGCCUUAGCUUUGUUGGUCUUUUUCUAUAAUUUACUCCACAACUUCCAAAAAAUAUUUUAAACUAGUUUAUCAUAAAACUCACACCAAGGGUUUCAAAACAUCCUUUUGUAAAGGUGAAAAGAAGACUGAGAAGCUGCAUAGGCUGCAGGCUGGGAGUGGAGAAGGAAAGACCUGCUGCAGCCAUGUGACUCAGGGGCCUGAGAGGUGAAUCAAAGCCUCCUUGUUGCCAGGGCUGAGACGGGGACAGGAUGGCUUCUAGGCUUCCUGUCUUUGGAUUUUAGUAGGAAGUUUCCAGGCUUUUGUUCUGAAACCCCCAGGUUGCUUCAUUUAGCUUCCGACCUCCCUGUAGGAGGAGGUGGGCACAGAACGUGUUUGGAAGCGUCUGGGAGAAUAAGGACCAGGCUAGAAAGAACCUUUGUUCUACCCUGACUCAGGCAUCGGCCAUCCUUUCAGAGCCCAUUUCCACCACAGUUGGAAGAAGUAGUUGGGGUUUAGAACCCUGUGAUUCCAACCCAUGCUGCCCCUCCAAGAAGACACGGGGCGAGGCCCGGCCAUACCAGUGUUGAGGUAAAGGAUCUGAGGCUGGCCAUCCUGGUAGAUGAAAAGAGGGUUCAACCCAGGAUGACCCCAAGCCUUUGGGUUAACUGCUGAGUUUGGUGUUUGCCCCAGAUAUUAUACCCCCUGACUGUUUCAGUGCUGUGCUCCACCUUCCUCCUGGCGUGGUGGGGAAGGGUAGCCAUGAAGCUCAGUUGGAGUAUAGAGGAGGAGCCUUCUGGCUUUGUGAGCUCCUGCCCCUGGGGUCCUGCGGUGGUGGUCACAAGUGACACAGAGCCAUGACAAGUAGCAUUGUUGAUGUUGAUGAUCAGAAUUAGUAAAAAUGGGCUGGUCGUGGUGGCUCAUGCCUGUAAUCCUAGCACUUUGGGAGGCCAAGGCAGGUGGAUCACUUGAGGUCAGGAGUUUGAGACCAGCCUGGCCCACAUGGUUAGGCCAUCUACUAAAAAUACAAAAAUUAGCCAGGCAUGGUGGUGGGUGCCUGUAAUCCCAGCUACUUGGGAGGCUGUGGCAGGAGAAUCACUUGAACCUGGGAGGCAGAGGUUGCAGUGAGCUGAGAUCAUGCCACUGCACUCUAGCCUGGGUGACAGAGGAAGACUCCAUCUCAAAAAAAAAAAAAAAAAAAAAGUAAAAAUGUAUAAAUCACAACACAUGGUAAGUAACACAAUACCAAUCAUAAUUCACUUCAAAAACAGCAGCUUGAAAUUAAUCAGCAGUUGUGUUGUUUCUUAGAAAUAUCAGAAGCCACACGCUGUGUCUGAAAGCUUGUGAGUAAGAAUGAGGAGGAGUGACAGGCAGAUCAGCCAACGAUAGAGGGGCUUCUGUGAUCUGGGCAGGUGUCGCUGGUCACUCCUGGCUCUGUGGGCGUGGUUAUGUCCUAACCCUGUGAGUUCUUGCUGCUGUCAGCACCGCAUGGAUGCAGGGAUUCCUGGCUGUUAGUUACAUGGCCAAGCAGCUUCUGAAAAUUAUCGUCUGUGGCCACAGAAAUCCUUGACUAAGUGCUACGGAGUCAUCAUUAUUAUCCCAUCACAUGAUUCUUCUUAAUCCUUUAGAAUCACUUGUUAAACUUUAAUAGGUAAGAUAAUUUCAUGCUCAUUGAAGUAAUGUAAUUAUACAGACUAAUUCAACGCUAUUAGAAAAUUUCUGGGCUCCAUUUAUAAUAACAGCUAAUGCAUUCUAAGUACAGUUUGUUAGGGAACCUUGCAUAUUCAACCCAAAAGAACCCCAGGUUUGCGCGUGAGCUUGGAUGCUGAGCAGUGUUGAGUGAACUGGAGCCUACUGGAAGCUGUUCCAUUUGUCCUUAGGUGACUUUUUUAGAAGUGAUUAGACUUGGGGAUUGUUUCUCAGAAAUGGACUGGAGACCCAUAAAUCUACAACGAUUUUAAUUUUGGACACCAACCUGGAGCCCACAAAGACAACUUCCCACGAGUUAGCAGCAGUGCUGGGCAGUAGGGGGGCACGUGUGCUGAGGCGUGGGCGUGCCAGCCUUGCAGUGGAGGAGGGGCUGCUCUUUGCCACGUGUCUGCAGCUCUCUUCCGGUCUCUGGCUUGAACAGACUGGGGAGCCUGAGGUCACAUUUUACUUGUCUUUUGGGAGGGAGGUUGGGGUAAUCUGGGGCAAGGGGCUCAGCCAGCUGCCACCCAGACUUGAGUGCUCUGUUUGGUGGCACCAGACAUGGUGAGGUGGGUGGUAUUGAGCAGGGUGGGGGAGGCAGCAAAAGCCAGGCCUACAGAAUUACACUUCUGUGGCCUAAUGAUUUUCAAAAACCAUUUGCGAGAUUGAGGUAAUGUAUUUCCCAGACUUAAGCAAUUUACUCCUUCCCACCGUGCUGAAUCAGGCUGUUAAAUCCUCUUGCUGUGUGCGUAGAGCUAUUGGCACCAGGGAAAAAUGGUCAAGUUCAAGGCCCCUGCCAAAUCUGUGCUCUUUUCUUUGGAAAGUGAUGAGUAACUGCACUUUAAAAAAAAAUGGGCUGGGCGUGGUGGCUCACGCCUGUAAUCCCAGCACUUUGGGAGGCCGAGGUGGGUGAAUCACCUGAGGUCGGGAGUUCGAGACCAGCCUGACCAACAUGGAGAAACCUUGUCUCUGCUGAAAAUACAAAAAAUUAGCCAGGCGUGGUGGCAUUUGCCUGUAAUCCCAGCUACUCUGGAGGCUGAGGCAGGAGAAUCACUUGAACCAGGGAGGUGGAGGUUGUGGUGAGCCGAGAUCGUGCCAUUGCACUCCAGCCUGGAAAACGAGCAAAACUCCGUCUCAAAAAAAAAAAAAAAAAAAGAAGAUUUUAGGAACAUUGGAAAAUGUUAAGUGAAGAAAGCAGGAUGCCAGAUUGUACAUUCAGUAGGAUCUCAGGAGAAACAAUGUCUGCAUAGAAAAAUACUGUGGAAACUGCCAGCAGGUUGCAGGGCUUACCUGUGCUUGAGUGCAAGGAUUAGAUCCAGUGUCCCCUCUGUUCCUUUUCAGCAUCUUACCCGUUGCCCAGGGUGGUGACACCUGGGCCCCAGGUGAGAAGCGCCCCAGAAAGAGAAGCACAUGCAUGCUGGCCGUGAGUCAUGGGCCUGCUAACUUGCUUGUCCUGUAACCUUGGGCAACUUCCUUCCUACUGGGAGCCCUAGUCUCUUCAUCUGUAUAGUGGCCCAGUUACACUAUCUCAGAGGAGUGAGGGUCACUGCCAGGACUCCGUCACCUGCGUAAACACCUGGCAAUGUGGGCAUGUGGCAGUCUAGAUAAACCAUAGCCUUGUGGUGGUGAUGGGGUCAUUAUAAAAAUGCAUUGUUUCUUUCACAACCAGGAAAACAUUACACAUAAAAGAACAGGGCAAUGACUGGAGGUGGAAAAACAACGCAGCCUACCUAGCUGCAUGGAGACCUAUGGGAACAUCCACUGGACCUUAACUUGGCUUAUGGGAGUCAGGAGGGCUUCCUGGCGGAAGGAGUGUCUCAUGGGAGACAGGAGAGAAGAGUAGGAGCCAACCAGGUGGAGACAGAGGAAUGUACUUCAAACAGAGAGAAGGCAUAUGUAAGGCUGGAGGUUCAAGGAACAGAGUGAGUUUGGGAAACGCACCUAGAAAGUGGCGUGCAAGGACGAUCGUGAUGGGAGAUGAGGCUGGGCAGGUAUGGAACGCCGUGGACUCCGGGCACUGCCUGCAGACCUACUCCCUGCACACAGAGGCAGUGCGGGCCGCCCGGUGGGCUCCCUGUGGCCGGCGCAUCCUCAGUGGUGGCUUUGACUUCGCGCUGCACCUAACAGACCUUGAAACAGGAACCCAGCUAUUUAGUGGUCGAAGUGACUUUAGAAUCACUACCUUGAAAUUCCAUCCAAAAGACCACAACAUCUUUUUAUGUGGAGGCUUCAGCUCUGAAAUGAAAGCUUGGGAUAUAAGGACUGGCAAGGUGAUGAGAAGCUACAAGGCGACCAUCCAGCAGACCUUGGACAUCCUGUUCCUCCGGGAAGGCUCCGAGUUCCUGAGCAGCACAGACGCUUCCACCCGGGACUCAGCUGACCGCACCAUUAUUGCCUGGGAUUUCCGGACCUCUGCCAAAAUCUCCAACCAGAUUUUCCACGAGAGGUUCACCUGCCCCAGCCUCGCCUUGCACCCGAGAGAGCCCGUGUUCCUGGCACAGACCAAUGGCAACUACCUGGCCCUUUUCUCCACUGUGUGGCCCUACCGGAUGAGCAGACGGCGGCGCUAUGAAGGGCACAAGGUGGAGGGCUACUCAGUGGGCUGCGAGUGCUCCCCAGGCGGUGACUUGCUGGUGACGGGCAGCGCCGAUGGCCGGGUCCUGAUGUACAGCUUCCGCACAGCCAGCCGAGCAUGCACACUGCAGGGGCACACACAGGCCUGUGUCGGCACCACCUAUCACCCCGUGCUGCCCUCCGUCCUCGCCACCUGCUCCUGGGGAGGGGACAUGAAGAUCUGGCACUGAGCUUUUUGUCACUGAACCUUCCCGAUGCCAGCUGGGCUCUUGGACUCCCCUCUUCCUCAAGGGUAGAUGAGAGGAACGAGCACAGAGGUUGGCUGUGGGUCCUGGGUACCACCUUCUGAGCCUCAGUUUCCUCAUCUGUAAAGUGGGGAGAAAAGUCUGUUUGCCUCAGGAGUGUGAGGACUACACUAGUGAAAGCGCCUGGCGGGCAGCCGGCGAUGCCCAAUAAAUGUGUGUUUUGCUGUUUGUUAAGUGAUUUCAGCAA